GCACUGUGGGAUGGAAACCGGAGCGGCGCGUCCUGGCAGGACCGGGCGGCGGCGGCGGCGGGGCCGGCGGCGGCCAGGGACCCGGGCUUAGGCUCGGCCAGGCCGGCUGAGGGGCGCGGGCGGCCAGCGGGCGGCGGACGCCGUCAUGAACGCGGCGGUGGUGAGGCGGACGCAGGAGGCGCUGGGGAAAGUGAUUCGGAGGCCGCCGCUGACCGAGAAGCUGCUGAGCAAGCCCCCGUUCCGCUACCUGCACGACAUCAUCACGGAGGUGAUUAGAAUGACUGGUUUCAUGAAGGGCCUCUACACAGACGCCGAGAUGAAGUCUGAUAAUGUGAAGGAUAAAGAUGCAAAAAUUAGCUUCCUACAAAAGGCCAUAGACGUGGUUGUAAUGGUGUCGGGAGAGCCACUGUUGGCCAAACCAGCCCGAAUCGUGGCGGGGCAUGAGCCUGAAAGAACAAACGAGCUGCUCCAGAUAAUUGGAAAAUGCUGUCUCAACAAGCUCUCUAGUGACGAUGCGGUGCGGAGGGUUUUAGCUGGAGAGAAGGGAGAAGUGAAAGGCCGGGCCUCACUGACCUCAAGAUCUCAGGAAUUGGAUAAUAAGAAUGUGCGAGAAGAAGAGUCCAGAGUUCACAAAAAUACAGAGGAUAGAGGAGACGCUGAAAUAAAAGAGAGAAGUACAAGCAGAGAUCGAAAACAGAAGGAAGAAUUGAAAGAAGACCGCAAGCCAAGAGAAAAGGACAAGGACAAGGAGAAGGCCAAGGAGAAUGGCGGAAACAGACACAGAGAAGGGGAGAGAGAGAGAGCCAAAGCCCGGGCCAGGCCAGACAACGAGCGACAGAAAGACAGAGGCAACAGGGAGCGGGACAGAGACUCCGAGCGCAAGAAGGAGACAGAGAGAAAGAGUGAGGGGGGGAAAGAGAAGGAGAGACUGAGAGACAGGGACCGAGAGCGCGACCGGGACAAAGGGAAGGACAGGGACAGACGGAGAGUGAAAAACGGGGAGCACUCCUGGGACCUGGACAGGGAGAAGAACAGAGAGCAUGACAAACCUGAGAAAAAGUCAGCAAGCUCAGGGGAGAUGUCUAAAAAGUUAUCAGAUGGAACUUUUAAAGACUCCAAGGCUGAAACAGAGACUGAGAUUUCCACUAGAGCUUCCAAGUCAUUGACAACAAAAACAUCAAAACGGCGAUCCAAAAAUUCAGUGGAAGGAAGAAGGGACCCUAAAACCAGUGAAAAUAGUCUUUCCCCUGAAAAGGAACAUAACUUUUCCUACUGUAAAGCUAAGAAGGAACAUAGCAUGAAACAGCUUGGAAGGAAGGAGGAUAAUAUUUCAGCUAAAAGUUUAGACUCCAUAGUGUCUGGAAUAAAUAAUGAGCCAAAUCAGGAAACGACAACAUCAGAAAUAGGAACAAAAGAAGCUAAUAUUAACUCAACUAGUAUUUCAGAUGAUAAUUCAGCUAGUCUGCGGUGUGAGAAUAUUCAGCCCAACCCCACAGAGAAGCAGAAAGGUGACUCCACCAGUGAUGCAGAAGGAGAUGCUGGACCUGCUGGCCAAGAUAAGUCUGAGGUGCCAGAGACUCCAGAAAUUCCUAAUGAGCUUUCAUCCAACAUCAGAAGAAUUCCUCGGCCUGGGAGUGCAAGACCAGCCCCUCCCCGGGUCAAACGGCAAGACAGCAUGGAGGCGCUACAAAUGGAUAGGUCAGGGAGUGGUAAAACCGUUUCAAAUGUGAUUACAGAGUCACACAAUUCUGACAAUGAAGAGGAUGAUCAAUUUGUGGUGGAAGCUGCCCCUCAGCUCUCUGAAAUGUCAGAAAUUGAAAUGGUAACAGCAGUGGAACUAGAAGAAGAGGAGAAGCAUGGUGGACUUGUGAAAAAAAUUUUGGAGACGAAGAAAGAUUAUGAGAAAUUGCAGCAGUCACCCAAACCUGGGGAGAAGGAGCGAUCUCUCUUUGAGUCGGCAUGGAAGAAGGAGAAGGACAUCGUUUCCAAGGAGAUAGAGAAGCUCCGCACGUCCAUCCAGACCCUGUGCAAGAGCGCACUUCCCCUGGGGAAGAUCAUGGACUACAUCCAGGAAGACGUGGAUGCCAUGCAGAAUGAGCUGCAGAUGUGGCACAGCGAGAACAGGCAGCACGCCGAGGCCCUGCAGCAGGAGCAGAGGAUCACAGACUGUGCCGUGGAGCCCUUAAAGGCUGAGCUCGCGGAGCUGGAGCAGCUGAUCAAAGACCAGCAAGACAAGAUCUGUGCUGUGAAGGCCAACAUCCUCAAGAAUGAAGAAAAAAUCCAGAAAAUGGUAUAUAGUAUCAAUUUGACUUCGAGAAGGUGAACACUCAAAAGUUUCAGAGAUGAAAAGUCACCUCAGUUUAAAAGCAAAAAGGAAGAUAGAAAAUCAUUACUCUUUUAAGUUCCAGUUUGCUAAGAAAAUGAACAGUUUACAAUGUUAUUAUCCAGCUAAUUUUCAGAGCUUUAAAACUGUAAGCAUGUUAAGUGUAUUAAAAAAACCAUGUUUUCUUACCUCCUUCCAGAUGGAAUACUGGCUAGUUAUAAAUAGCGCUUCCAAACACCUCUGUGAAAAGUUUUUUUGAAAGCCUGUUCUUUGUGUUUCUGCUGUAACCUGUUUAGUUCUGUACCAGAACUCUCUAGCAGGUAAGUGGUGUGGGCAUACCAAGGGAACAGUAGUCCUUUAUUUUGGUUUAGUGGAAAGACUUUCAGAGGUCAGUGCCGAAUGAAGGAUGACUGUGUACUUUUUGAUAGGCACUUGAUAAGUAGAAUGAGGCCUGAAAAUGAAUACAUUAUAUUUUUAGUUAAUUUCCAAUGGAAAGGGCUAACCUCAGCCUGUCUCCAUAUCAGGUACCUAUCAACUGGAUUGUUUUCAUUUUUGUUUUUUGACCUCUUUGUAAUUGCAUGUACUUCUCUAUGUAAUUUUCCUCUUGAUCUCUACUAUCGUUUGCUUGUGUUUCUAGUCCUUAAAGUUCAUAAAUUUAAAAAGGAGAUUUCAGGAUGGCCUUUAUGGACGUUGUCUGGACAUACAUCCUCACUUUCUUCCGCAGUUUACCCUGGUUUUCCUCAGACAGAGGCUAGCGCAGCCCCCCGGAGUCCUUGUUCUCCUUAAGAGGGUCUCGCUCUGCAAAGCAUUGGCGCCAUGGCUUUUCCUUUGCAUGGGUGUGCAUACCGAGAGACAGGCAGCUUAGGAAAAACAACAUAAGGAAGACUUAAAAGGAUGCACUGAUUUACGACGUUUUUUGAUGUUAGCCAUUUUUUUGGAAAUUGUUUUUUAAAGCAAAAGUUUUUUAAAAACAUGGUUUAUAGUUUUUCACUUACAUAUACUAUUGUAAAUACUUAGCAGAGUCUUAAGUUACUGUAUAAAACAUUUCAUUGUGUUUGAAGACAUACUUAUGGGUCUUGAGGUCUGGGUCCUAAUACUUUUAAAUAGUGUAUUUAUUAUGUAAACUGAGGAGUGCCAUUUAAAGUGUGAGGAUUGCCUGAAAAGGUUUUGUUUCUUUCUUUUUUUUUUUUUUUUGAGAUGGAGUCUUACUCUGUCGCCCAGGCUGGAGUGCAGUGGCGCAAUCUCGGCUCACUGCAACCACCGCCUCCCGAGUUCAAGUGAUUCUCCUGCCUCAGCCUCCUGAGUAACUGGGACUACAGGCGCACGCCACCAUGCCCAGCUAAUUUUUGUAUUUUCAGUAGAGAUGGGGUUUCACCGUGUUGACCAGGAUGGUCUCCACCUCCUGACCUCGUGAUCCGCCUGCCUCGGCCUCCCAAAGUGCUGGGAUUACAGGCAUGAGCCACUGCACCCGGCCAGGUUUUGUUUCUUUAAGGAUUAGCACAAAUGGCACCGUUGGGUUUUUCUUCAUACAAUUUCCAAAAUAAAUUCUGUACUCAGGUUGUUAUAUGAUUUUCUGAGCUGAAUAAGUUCAGGAGCAGAUUAUUAAGAUCUGCCAUUCUGAAACGCUGGUCUUUUUCUCCUUCCUAUAGUGCACCAUAAAAUUCUGUUUGAUCAGAUUAUAUUACAUACAUUUUGGGGGAGUGGAGGGACAUGAGUUAAGUAGCCCUUCAUGUAUUUAUAAUCUCUUUUCUACUGAAUCAAAUGACUUAGCCAUGACCCUGAAUGGACCUUGUUUUACUUCAAGUUGAGAUGUCUGCCUUUUAUGAAUUUGUAUAUGUGAAUAGAGUUUGGGGGUUGCCAAAAAUUGCAUACAUUGUAUGUAAGUAAAAUUUUUUAUGAAGUAGUCUGUCAAAUUGUAUCAUAAAGUUUAUUUUUCUUUUAUACGUAAAUCAUUAAAAAUAAUCACAUAUUUUUUCCAUAA